GGCCCCAGGGUGGGAAGGGGCCAGAGUGGAGAGAUGCUGCUGCGGAAGUCCUCGGUGGAGUGUGAGAAGGCAGCCAGUGUUGGCCUGGAAGACCUCUAGAACCUGAGAAGAGGCAGCGAUCCUGGGGCAGAGUCCAGGGCAGCUCAAGGCUCCUCCACACACACACCCGCUGAACCCUGAGCACCCUGAGCUGCUGAGAUGGGGCGGGCCGGGGCUGCCGCCGUGAUCCCGGGCCUGGCCCUGCUCUGGGCAGUGGGGCUGGGGAGUGCCGCCCCCAGCCCCCCACGCCUUCGGCUCUCCUUCCAAGAGCUCCAGGCCUGGCAUGGUCUCCAGACUUUCAGCCUGGAGCGAACCUGCUGCUACCAGGCCUUGCUGGUGGAUGAGGAGCGUGGACGCCUGUUUGUGGGUGCCGAGAACCAUGUGGCCUCCCUCAACCUGGACAACAUCAGCAAGCGGGCCAAGAAGCUGGCCUGGCCGGCCCCUGUGGAAUGGCGAGAGGAGUGCAACUGGGCAGGGAAGGACAUUGGUACUGAGUGCAUGAACUUCGUGAAGUUGCUGCAUGCCUACAACCGCACCCAUUUGCUGGCCUGUGGCACGGGAGCCUUCCACCCAACCUGUGCCUUUGUGGAAGUGGGCCACCGGGCAGAGGAGCCCGUCCUCCGGCUGGACCCAGGAAGGAUAGAGGAUGGCAAGGGGAAGAGUCCUUAUGACCCCAGGCAUCGGGCUGCCUCCGUGCUGGUGGGGGAGGAGCUAUACUCAGGGGUGGCAGCAGACCUCAUGGGACGAGACUUUACCAUCUUUCGCAGCCUAGGGCAACGUCCAAGUCUCCGAACAGAGCCACACGACUCCCGCUGGCUCAAUGAGCCCAAGUUUGUCAAGGUAUUUUGGAUCCCGGAGAGCGAGAACCCAGACGACGACAAAAUCUACUUCUUCUUUCGUGAGACGGCGGUAGAGGCGGCGCCGGCACUGGGACGCCUGUCCGUGUCCCGCGUUGGCCAGAUCUGCCGGAACGACGUGGGCGGCCAGCGCAGCCUGGUCAACAAGUGGACGACGUUCCUGAAGGCGCGGCUGGUGUGCUCGGUGCCCGGCGUCGAGGGCGACACCCACUUCGAUCAGCUCCAGGAUGUGUUUCUGUUGUCCUCGCGGGACCACCGGACCCCGCUGCUCUAUGCCGUCUUCUCCACGUCCAGCAGCAUCUUCCAGGGCUCUGCGGUGUGCGUGUACAGCAUGAACGACGUGCGCCGGGCCUUCUUGGGACCCUUUGCACACAAGGAGGGGCCCAUGCACCAGUGGGUGUCAUACCAGGGUCGCGUCCCCUACCCGCGGCCAGGCAUGUGCCCCAGCAAGACCUUUGGCACCUUCAGUUCCACCAAGGACUUCCCAGACGAUGUCAUCCAGUUUGCGCGGAACCACCCCCUCAUGUACAACUCUGUCCUGCCCACUGGGGGGCGCCCUCUUUUCCUACAAGUUGGAGCCAAUUACACCUUCACUCAAAUUGCCGCGGACCGGGUUGCAGCCGCUGACGGACACUAUGACGUCCUCUUCAUUGGCACAGACGUUGGCACGGUGCUGAAGGUGAUCUCGGUCCCCAAGGGCAGUAGGCCCAGCGCAGAGGGGCUGCUCCUGGAGGAGCUGCACGUGUUUGAGGACUCGGCCGCUGUCACCAGCAUGCAAAUUUCUUCCAAGAGGCACCAGCUGUACGUAGCCUCGCGGAGCGCGGUGGCCCAGAUCGCGUUGCACCGCUGCGCUGCCCACGGCCGCGUCUGCACCGAAUGCUGUCUGGCGCGUGACCCCUACUGCGCCUGGGACGGGGUCGCGUGCACGCGCUUCCAGCCCAGUGCCAAGAGGCGGUUCCGGCGGCAAGACGUAAGGAAUGGCGACCCCAGCACGUUGUGCUCCGGAGACUCGUCUCGUCCCGCGCUGCUGGAACACAAGGUGUUCGGCGUGGAGGGCAGCAGCGCCUUUCUGGAGUGUGAGCCCCGCUCGCUGCAGGCGCGCGUGGAGUGGACUUUCCAGCGCGCAGGGGUGACAGCCCACACCCAGGUGCUGGCAGAGGAGCGCACCGAGCGCACCGCCCGGGGACUACUGCUGCGCAGGCUGCGGCGCCGGGACUCGGGCGUGUACUUGUGCGCCGCCGUCGAGCAGGGCUUUACGCAACCGCUGCGUCGCCUGUCGCUGCACGUGUUGAGUGCUACGCAGGCCGAACGACUGGCGCGGGCCGAGGAGGCUGCGCCCGCCGCGCCGCCGGGCCCCAAACUCUGGUACCGGGACUUUCUGCAGCUGGUGGAGCCGGGCGGAGGUGGCAGCGCGAACUCCCUGCGCAUGUGCCGCCCGCAGCCUGCGCUGCAGUCACUGCCCCUGGAGUCGCGGAGAAAGGGCCGUAACCGGAGGACCCACGCCCCUGAGCCUCGCGCUGAGCGGGGGCCGCGCAGCGCAACGCACUGGUGACCAGACUGUCCCCACGCCGGGAACCAAGCAGGAGACGACAGGCGAGAGAGGAGCCAGACAGACCCUGAAAAGAAGGACGGGUUGGGGCCGGGCACAUUGGGGGUCACCGGCCGAUGGAGACACCAACCGACAGGCCCUGGCUGAGGGCAGCUGCGCGGGCUUAUUUAUUAACAGGAUAACCCUUGAAUGUAGCAGCCCCGGGAGGGCGGCACAGGUCGGGCGCAGGAUUCAGCCGGAGGGAAGGGACGGGGAAGCCGAGCUCCAGAGCAACGACCAGGGCCGAGGAGGUGCCUGGAGUGCCCACCCUGGGAGACAGACCCCACCUCCUUGGGUAGUGAGCAGUGAGCAGAAAGCUGUGAACAGGCUGGGCUGCUGGAGGUGGGGCGAGGCAGGCCGACUGUACUAAAGUAACGCAAUAAACGCAUUAUCAGCCAAAGCUGGAAUGGCCCCAGCAGAAAACCCCAGUCCUCGGCCUUGCUAUGUGGUCUUGGGCACCUUACUAGCGGUGUCAGGGCCCGAGUUUCUCCUGUCCAAGGUUGCCUGGUGAGGAUUAAAGGUGGUUCCGGCCAGGCGCGGUGGCUCACGCCUGUAAUCCCAACACUUUCGGAGGCCCAGGCGGACGGAUCACGAGGUCAGGAGAUGGAAACCAUCCCGGCUAACACGGUGAAACCCCGUCUGUACUAAAAAUACAAAAAAUUAGUCGGGCGUGGUGGCGGGCGCCUGUAAUCCUAGCUACUCAGGAGGCUGAGGCAGGAGAAUUGCUUGAACCUGGGAGGUGGAGGUUGCAAUGAGCCUAGAUCUCGCCGCUGCACUCCAGCCUGGGCGACAGAGCGAGACUCC